UGAUCCGCCCGCCUUAGCCUCCCAAAAGUGCUGGGAUCAAAAGUGUGAGCCACCGAGCCUGGGUCAGCAGUGAGUUUUUAAGGUUGCCUUACAGAGUACCACUUGAUAGUUGACCCCUGAUCAUUUAGCAUUUUGUAAGUGUAAAAAAAAAAAAACUUACCUGAAGUAUUCUCAAUGGUCUUUUUUUCAAACAUUCUUCCCUACACCAAGGGCAGAGAAACCUUUAGAAAUUACACAUACGUGGCCAGGCGCGGUGUCUCGCGCCUGUAAUCCCAGCACUUUGGGAGGCCGAGGCGAGCGGAUCACGAUGUCAAGAGAUCCUGGCCAACAUGGUGAAACCCCGUCUCUACUAAAAAUACAAAAAUUAGCCGGGCGUGGUGGCGGGCUCCUGUAGUCCCAGCUACUCGGGAGGCUGAGGCAGGAGAAUCGCUUGAACGCGGGAGGCUGAGGUUGCAGUGAGCCGAGAUCGCGCCACUGCACUCCAUCCUGACGACAGAACGAGAAUCUGUCUCAAAAGAAAAAAAAAAUUACACAUGUGUGUCUCGCCUGUGUUUGGUUCCUGUGUUGGUGCCUCUGGAUAUUUGUCAAACUAGAGUUCCUACAUUCCUUAUCAGGUUAUUUCUGUCGAAUCUCUAGCACUUUUAAGUGACGUAUAAUCUUGUAGGCAAGUGAAUGAAGUCAGUGAGUAUAUGUCACAUUGACUUACUCCUGACUCACAUGCAGCUUGUCUUUAGAUGGGCAGAUAAGAUGCUGGCCCUACUGGAGCGACUGUGGUUGUGCCGUCCUGAGCACCCUUCCUCCAGUGGCCCCGGUUUUCAAGGCUUUGACACAAUGGACCUAAAGUCUCCUUUUUCAAGCUUGGCUGCAUAUCCACAGUGCUUUUGUGCAUGAUGUUACGUUGUUCUGGAGGUUUCAUUUUGUAAUUCCAGUUACCUUUGAUGAAAGAAAUUAGUAAAAACUUUUUGGAUGUGAGUAAUUGCAGAAGCCAUGUGGCUGCUGAGUUUCUACGUAAGCCUUGGGGUAAAAAGACACUGAGAUUCUCUCCUUUGUUCCAGGAAGUCCCGGAAUUUCCUAUUUUUCUAUUUUCUCUGUGUGUUUUAUUUUUUUUCCUUCCCUGAAAGCUUUGGAAAUGCCUGAGGAGAGACCUGGAAUGGCCAAAUAUCAAGGUGAAGUUCAAAGUUUGAAACUGGAUGAUGAUUCAGUUAUAGAAGGAGUAAGCGACCAAGUACUUGUGGCAGUUGUGGUCAGUUUCGCUUUGAUUGCUACCCUGGUAUAUGCACUUUUCAGAAAUGUACAUCAAAACAUUCACCCAGAAAACCAGGAGCUAGUAAGGGUACUUCGAGAACAGCUUCAAACAGAACAGGAUGCACCUGCUGCCACUCGACAGCAGUUCUACACUGACAUGUACUGUCCCAUCUGCCUGCACCAAGCCUCCUUCCCGGUGGAGACCAACUGUGGACAUCUUUUUUGUGGUGCCUGCAUUAUUGCUUACUGGCGAUAUGGUUCAUGGCUUGGGGCAAUCAGUUGUCCAAUCUGUAGACAAACGGUAACCUUACUCCUAACAGUAUUUGGUGAAGAUGAUCAGUCUCAGGAUGUUCUGAGAUUGCAUCAGGAUAUUAAUGAUUAUAACCGGAGAUUCUCAGGGCAACCCAGAUCUAUUAUGGAGAGAAUUAUGGAUCUACCCACUUUACUGAGGCAUGCAUUCAGGGAAAUGUUUUCAGUCGGGGGCCUUUUCUGGAUGUUUCGCAUCAGGAUAAUACUUUGUUUAAUGGGAGCUUUUUUCUAUCUUAUAUCACCUCUAGAUUUUGUACCUGAAGCCUUGUUUGGAAUUCUAGGCUUUCUAGAUGAUUUCUUUGUCAUCUUUUUAUUGCUUAUCUACAUCUCUAUUAUGUAUCGAGAAGUGAUAACCCAAAGGCUAACUAGAUGAAAAAGAAAACAAAACUGAGUUUACUAGGAUAUCUGAGCUAAUGUAGAACAUCAAACAGAAGGACCCAUGGCAGUAUAAAGCAAUGAAGCAAUGGAGUAUUAUCUCACAAAUAUAAAACCACUAUAAGACAAACAUUUGAUUAUCAUUUGACAAAUACCUAGGUAUAACUGGAAUUUUCAUGUUUGAAGUUCUAAUAUUAAGUUUAGAAUUAUAAUGAUCUACAGUUGUAUCUUGAUUCUAUGUUGUCUGGAAAAAAUAUGGAAUUAUAUAAAAAGGGAUGCUUUUAUAUAUUUUUCUUUUCCCCAGAAUUACUUAGAUUAAUUAGAUGUAUAGUAAAAUAUUGUUAAAUGUCAGUUUAUCCAUCUUAUCCUUCUCAGCAGGUACCUAUAUGAUAAUAUAUAGCUGUGAAACUCAUCUAAAUAUUUUUGUUCCAAUAAAAUAUUAUAUACUAUUGGGGAAAAUUCAGUAUUUCUUUUAGUGCUAGCUAAGUUUUGUGCAUUUGGAGCAGUUCUGCCUUUUCAUUCUGGUAUAAUUAAUUAUUUGCUAUCAGCUGAAACUGAAAGAAGAAACUUGAACUUCAUACUUCGAUAUCAUAUUCUAGUUUACAGAACACAUUUUAAUCAAUAGAAGAAUUAAGAUGAAAAACAUGGCCGGGCGGGGUGGCUCACGCCUGUAAUCCUAGCACUUUGGGAGGCUGAGGCGGGUAGAUCACAAGGUCAGGAGAUCAGGACCAUCCUGGCUAACAUGGUGAAACCCCGUCUCUACUAAAAAUACAAAAAAUUAGCCAGGCGUGGUGGCAGGCGCCUGUAGUCCCAGCUACUCGGGAGGCUGAGGCAGAAGAAUGGCGUAAACCCAGGAGGUGGAUUGCGCCACUGCACUCCAGCCUGGGCAACAGAGUGAGACUCCCUCUCAAAAAAAAAAAAAAAAAAGAUGAAAAACAUUUAUCUCCAGUCAGCACACUUGAUGUUCACAGUUAGACAUUUAAACAAGAGCUCAUCCUUUCGUAGUAGAUAUAAAAGUAAUUUGUAAAGGGAAGAUUGUUUUAGGAACCUGGGCGAUGCUGCAAACACAGAGUAGCCUGAUGCAUUUCUGAGGAAGGUGAAUCUUCGUGUCUUUGAGCAUCAAGCCAAUAGGAAGGUACUGGGAACGGUAUUUACAUUUGACAAAAGAAAUUACUGGUUAGCUAUAGCAACAGAUUGGACAAAUUUUGUUAGUUUUCUGUUGUCAGAAAUUUUUAUAAUACUGUCUCAGGAUGGCAGCACACAGCUCAGAUUCAUGUCUUGAGCCAAACAAGUGAAUGUAUCUGAGAAGACUCAGUACCACAUGGUACUGGGAGAUCUUACUCACUUCAGCUGGCGUUGCUCAUUAGUGAAUGUAUGACAGCAGGAUGUGAGGGGAUGCCCAGGAGUCAGUGUUAGCAUUGUCAUCUGAGAUCACUGCUAUUAAUAUCAUCCAUUAAUUUAUUAGUGAGCUUCACUAUAUGCAGACUGGGAGAUAAGGAGAAAAUCUGUCACAUUCUCUCUAGCUAAUCAGAUCAGCUACCAAUUAAUGAGAUUCUGAAUGAAAUAUCAAUAUGUGUUUUUCUAAUUUGGACCUAGGACAGAGCUGUUGCUUGUCAUAGAGAAAAACAAUAAUGCUUAAACAUAGCACAUUAUAAUUAAAGCAGGUUUCUCACAUACUUUUCAUUUUAUCCUUUGGAUAAUUUUGUGAGGAACGCAGGACACCAACUUCCCUUUCAUAGAUACAAUCCCCAUGCUAUUGAUGAAAGUGUUUUUGAAUGAAGUCAUACAACAAAUAACUGAUCAAAGUGGCAUUACACCAAAAUUUCUUAGUAGGACUCCUGCAUAGAAUGUUUAGAUAGACGUGAAAGUUGUUAAGAGGAACAGCAAGAGAGAAACUGGUUCUUUGGAAGUCUUUCGUGCUACAUUAUACCUCCAUCAGAGUAAGACAGCUUAGGCACUCCUAAGAGGAAAGGUCUGUGGAGAUGACAUGAAUCCGAAUUCUACACUUCCAAAUCAAAUAGGUAAAAGGGUGGCAUACAUCACAGAAAAACAUUUCAGCUGCAGUCACCAACUUGAAAAGCGAGUGAGUAGGAGUUUGUCACACUGCCAUGUACCAGACUGGAAAUGCAUUUCCUACCAAUUACACAUUUGGUGUGGGGGAAUGGUGAUGUCAUUUUUUGACAGGAUUUUAUUUUGUGUGCAUGCAUUCUGCUCCAAGUGUCACAAUUCUGGUUACAAUAAUUAUAAUAUUUGGAGUUACUACUAAGACUUUCCUGAAAGAGGUGUAUUGUACCAAAUUUUGUAACAUAAAAAAAUACUAAAUGAUCUUAAAGCUUCCUAAAUUGUGAAAAGGGUAUGUGCUAACAUCUCAGAACUUUAGACCUGCUUGUUGUCAUCUUUACCGAUCUCUGAUGAUAAAUGCAGAAGGGAUCUGAGAGUUUUUAAAGCAAGUAGAGUCAAUCAGAGUUUUGAACAUCAUAGUAAUACUUCCGUGAUUCAGAGUUAGAUCAUAUAAAUCAAAGUAACAAUUUGGAUUUUUUUUAAACAACAAUAUCAUAACUGUCAUAAAACAGAUGGUCCAACCCCAGGAGCAGAUAAUAACUUGGGCAGCUCUGUGGGGAACAAGACGGGGAAAACAACUGUUCUAACUGCCCACUAGAACAGUGGUUUCAACUACUACAAUUCUCAGUGUUUGAGAGGUACAAGGGAAGAAAGGACUAUGUGGAUCCCUUGUGGCUAUGCAGAUACCUACCUCACAGAGUUGUUGUAGAAGACUGGUGGUUUGGUUCAAACCUUGUGAUUAAAGAGUUUGUCAAGCAUUUUAUUCUUUUGAAUAAAAGCAACAUAUCUAAAACA